UCACUGAUAGAUAGUUGAAUAUUUCACAAUUUAUUUAUAAAUCCUCUUGUCAAAGAACAUUUUUGUUGUUUUCAGGGGCUUUUUUUGACACCAUUAAAAACUGAUGCAAUAAACAGUCUUAUAUAUCCCAGUGCAAAUGUACAAGAGGUUUUUUAAUGUAGAUACUACAUUUCAUUUAGUUUAAGAUCCAUUUUUUUACAUUUCAAUAUCUCUGAAACCAGAAUAUGUAUUAAAAUUAAUGACAUCUUAGAGUAUAAUUAGCAGCUUUUUAUUCCUUGAUGAUACAUUUGUAAAUGGCACAUCUUAAUGCAGUAUUAGAUUUUGAUGGAAUAUUGUAAAUAAGAGCAGAAUUGCUAGAUGUUAGGUAUUUUCAUCUUUCUGUUGACCAGGUUACUCUCCAUAGUGAUCGUAUUAGUUGCUGCUUGCUGAUCACACAUGGGAACUCCUGUUGUCUGAUGUCCUCACCAAUAUUUAAUAUCACUGAUUUUUUGCCAAUCUGGGUAGAUGCGGAAUGGUCUCUUAUUGUCAUUUUAUUUUGCCUUUCUCUCUUUACUAAUGAGGUUGAAUAUCUUUUCAGUUGCUUAGGGAAAAAUAUGAUUCUAUUGAGAAAUGCCUAUUUUGUCUUUGCUUAUUUUUCCAUUGAGUUGCUGUUCUUUCUCAAAUUAAUUUACGGGGGGUUUUAAAAUUAGUUUUAAAUAACCAUAAUAACCCUUUGUCUGUUAUAUGGGUUACAAACAUCUUUUUCUAAAUUGUGGCUUGCCUCCUCUCUUUAUGGAAUCUUUUGAUGAUCAGAAAUUAUUACAGUAAAAAUGAUUGAAAUUAUCAAACUUUUAUUUAAUGGUGUUUGUCUUUGGGAAUAUUCUAAAGACAUCCUUUCCUAUUCAGGAUCAUGAAAAUAUUAACUAUUUUAUCUUUAAAGAAUGUUUUAAAGUUUUACCUUUUGCGUUUAAGGUUUUAGAUUAUCUGGAGUUGAUUUGUAGGUAUGGUAAGGAAAAGGUGUCUAAUUUUGGUUUUUAAAAUAAUGGUAGCUAAUUGUCCCAGCGUAAUUUAUUGUAGUUUGUAAAAUGUUGUGUUUAUUGUGUAUAUCCACUGACAGAUAGUCUCACCUCAUUAUUUUUCACAUUUCCAUAUAUGUGAGGGUCUCUUUUUGGGUUCCUUAUUCUUUUCCACUAGCCUGUUUUUGUUUAUUUCUGUAGCAAUGACCUACCUUUCUUCUCACCUUUAUAAUAAGUUUUGAUAUCUGAUAGGGCAGAUCCCUGGCUACGUCUGCCUUUGUAGAUCUACCUUUCUCCAAAUGGCAGUCUUGUUGAUAACUGCUGCCUACCUAGGUUUGACUUAUCCUCUCCCGCUCACACAUACAAAGGGGCUGCUGUUGUCUGGUGCACAGAGAACUCCACAGUGAGCUGAGAAGCAGCAUUGCAGGCUGUGGGAAUGUCCUCUAAGAAGGACCUGAGAGUCCAGCCUCAGGUCCAGAUGGGGUCAGGGUUAUUGAGCCCAUUUCGCAGAUGAGGAAACCAAGAGGAGGUAAGUGACUCGCUUGGCUCCCAGUGCUGGGCCGUGGUGGAGCUGGCCUUGAUCACGGUCCAGCUGGGUAUUGCCACUGCAGAAUUGCUGACCUCUAAAUAGAACCGUGUUUCUCAUGAUCUCAGAACUUCAUUUACUCAAAUGAGUUUCGCCACCACGCUUCAGAAGCAUUCUUUAGCCUAGGCUAGCAGUUUUCCUGUAAAUCAGUCUCAUGUUCAGCCCCACUCAGCCCUGUUGGACCUGUUUUUCAAGCAUCAAGAGGUUCAUUCCUUGCUCUUUCUUCCCACACACGCUUCUCCUUUUUUUUAUACUUAAAUAAUUAUUUUGAUGCUUCUAAAACUCCCCAAGAUUAGUAAGUGUAUUUAUUGGUAAGUAUUAUCUCUCUCUUUGUCUAGAUAUCUGGAAAUGCUAAAUCUGGUGUUCGCUCCUUCUUUUUCCUGUUCCUGAGGCCUGGUUGACCCGCGGCCUAUGGCUUCUCAGGCACCUCUCCUUCCCCGUCUCUCUCUACAUAGCAGAGACAAAGGAAAGGCCAUACUGGGACCUGGCAGGAGAGCUGUAAUUAGUGAAGCUAAUGCUUUGUCUCACUCUAAAGUUCAAGUUCAUUAGUGAAACUUCCUUUAUCUUGUCUUCCUGGUUUCUGGUUUCUGAUGAGCUCGUACUUAUUUUGCAAUCAAGGGUAAAAAUGUUAAAUUAUAAUAGUAACUAGCAUCAUUAACUUUUUAAAGAAAGUUAACUGCACAUAAGCUCCACAAGGGCAGAGACUUUUCUGGCUGUUUUGCUCAUGCCGUGACUUUGAUACCUGGACCAAUGCCUGGCCCAUGGUCAAUGCUAUCUAAAUAUUUGCCGGAUAAAUAAAAAAUAAAUUGUAUUAGGUGCUUCCUACAUGCCAGGCAGCGUGCUAAGGGCUUUCUAUGUGUCUUCUUUCUUAGCUCUCAUAAUAAUCUGAUGAAAUAGACAUCACAAUCCCUGUUUCGCAGAUGGGGAAGCUGAGGCCUAGAGAAGUUAGGUGACUUGUCUAAGUCACAGAUUUUAUAAGUGACCAAGCUAGAUGCAAACCCAUGUCUGUGGGACACCAAAGAACAUUCUCUCAGCCCCCUUGUCAGAAAUGACAGAAAUGCUCUGCCAUUGAAGGUGCAGAGAUACGAGAUGCUGCCUUACGGAGUCUGAGAAUCGUCACUGCUUCUUUCACUCAUUGGCAGGGGUAGGGAGGCGUCAUUAAGCACCUUUUCCCCAGAAAUCCUAAGAAAAGACAAACAGCCCAGUUAUAAAAUGAGCAAAGGAUCUGGAUAGACAUUUUUCCAAAGAAGAAAGGCAAAUGGCCAAUAAGCACAUGAAAAGAUGCUCCACAUCAUUAGCCAUUAGGGAAAUGCAAAUCAAAACCACAAUGAGAUACCACUUCACACCCGCUGGAAUGGCUAUAAUCCAAAAGACGACAAUAACAACUGUGAGGAAGGCUGGCGAAAAAUGAAACCCUCAUACAUCGCUGGUGGGAAUGCAAAAUGGUACACUUUGGGAAACAGUCUGGCAAUUCCUCAAAUUUAAAUGUGGUAUGUGGUGUGAUCAUACGACACGGCAAUUCCACUCCUAGGUUAUGUAUAAGAAUAGAACACAUAUAUCACUCAAAAACUUGUGCAUGAAUUUUCACAGUAGUAGUAUUAUAAACCCACAGGGGGAACAACUCAAGUGUCCAUCAGCUGUUGAAGAGAUGCAACAUAGGUGGUCUACCUAUGCCCUGGAAUAUUAUUCAGCCUUAAGAAGCAAGGAUGUCCUGAUACGUGUUAUAGCAUAGAUGAACUUUGAAAGCAUUAUGAUAAGCAGAAGAAGCCAGAAACAAAAGCCCACAUAUUAUAUGAUUCAAUUUAUAGGAUAUGUCCAGAAUGGAUAACUCCAGAGAGAGACAGUUGUUGAGUGGUUGCCAGGGGCUGAGGUCAAGGGAUCAUGUGGAGUGCUACUAACAGGAUUACGGGACAGCUACCACAGUAGAAGAGAUCAAAUUGCCCUUAAAAAUCUCCAGUCUGAUGUCACAGAGGCAAAAUCUGACUUCACCAAGGAGACCCUGGCAUCACAAAACACAAAAAUGAUUUCAUCCAUAGUCAUCUCCCAGAUGAUUGAUGAGAAUAAGUCAAGAGAAAACAGGGCCUCCUUGCCCCUACCGUGUGCCAUUGCUCAGUCUCGUGCACAUCACGCCAAGCAAUCUCUGGCUAACCGCAGCGGAGUCAACAUUCACAGAGCAUUUGCGUUACUUCCGGGCAGAUUAGGAAUCCCGGCACCGUCAGAUGAGCGAGGACCUGAGGCAGAGCUGCCGCCCAAAGAGGAGAGACCCUGUGGGGGCCCCCGCAGAGGGUUUGCAUCCAUCACCAUCACGGCCAGACGCGUGGGCCCCCCAGCCCGCGCCCUGGUGUGGGGGACUGCUGGGGACUCUCUGUGCCCCAAGUGCAGGGCUGAGGACACACUGUUCCAGGCGCCCCCGGCUCUGGCCAAUGGCGCCCAUCCAGGUCGGCAUCAGAGAUCUUUUGCCUGCACAGAGUUCUCCAGAAACAGCUCCGUGGUGCGGCUGAAGGUUCCCGAGGCCCACACUGGGUUGUGUGAGAGACGCAAGUACUGGGUCACCCAUGCAGACGACAAAGAGACCAGUUUUUCUCCAGACACCCCACUGUCAGGAAAGAGCCCGCUGGUGUUCAGUUCCUGUGUCCACCUCAGGGUGUCUCAGCAGUGUCCAGAUUCAAUCUAUUACGUAGACAAGUCUCUCUCCGUCCCCAUUGAGCCACCUCAAAUUGCCAGCCCCAAAAUGCACAGAUCCGUCCUGUCGCUCAACCUCAAUUGUAGUUCCCACAGAUUAACAGCAGAUGGAGUAGAUGGCCUAGUGAACAGAGAGCCAAUAAGCGAAGCCCUGAAGCAGGAGCUCCUGGAGGGAGACCAGGACCUCGUAGGCCAGCGCUGGAACCCAGGUUUACAAGAAAGUCACUUGAAGGAAACCCCAUCGUUGAGGCGGGUGCAUUUGGGGACCGGCGCUUGUCCUUGGAGUGGUUCUUUUCCAUUGGAAAACACAGAAUUGGCAAAUGUGGGAGCUAACCAAGUCACUGUAAGAAAAGGGGAAAAGGACCAUACAACUCAUUGUCACGCCAGCGAUCAUGCCAACCAACUGUCCAUUCACAUUCCUGGCUGGAGUUACAGGGCAGUACACACAAAAGUAUUUUCUGGAAGCAGCAAGAGGCAACAAGGAGAAGUAUGUAUGACUGUGUCUGCUCCUCCAGUGGAACAGAAGCCCACUAGACAUUUCCUUCCCAUUGGGGAUAGCUCUCCAAGCGAUGACUGUCUGUCUAGAGACCUUUCUGAGCCCACAGAGAGACGACAUCAAAGCUUCCUGAAACCCAGAAUCCUUUUUCCUGGGUUUCUUUGCCCCUUACAAGAUGUAUGUGCAUCUCUGCAGGAAGACAAUGGUGUUCAGAUAGAAAGCAAGUUCCCCAAAGGAGAUUACACAUGCUGUGACUUGGUUGUAAAAAUAAAGGAAUGUAAGAAGAGUGAGGACCCCACCACACCUGAGCCCUCCCCAGCAGCACCCUCGCCAGCACCCCGCGAUGGAGCAGGGAGCCCUGGCCUGUCCGAAGACUGUUCUGAGUCUCAGCAAACGCCUGCAAGAUCUUUGACCUUGCAAGAAGCACUGGAAGUUCGUAAGCCUCAGUUCAUUUCUCGCUCACAAGAACGGCUGAAGAAGCUUGAACACAUGGUCCAGCAGAGGAAAGCCCAGCGGAAGGAGGACCUGAGGCAGAAGCAGAGCCUCCUUCCCAUCCGCACCAGCAAGAAGCAGUUCACGAUUCCCCAUCCUCUGAGUGAUAACUUGUUCAAACCCAAAGAACGGUGCAUUUCAGAGAAGGAGAUGCAUAUGCGAUCUAAGAGAAUCUAUGAUAACUUGCCGGAAGUUAAAAAGAAAAAAGAAGAACAAAGGAAAAGGGUGAUCUUACAAAGUAACAGACUCCGUGCCGAAGUCUUCAAAAAGCAAUUACUGGACCAGCUCCUUCAAAGGAAUGCGGUCUAACCACAGGCUGCCCUGCUGACCACACUACCUGGACCUGGGAGGACUUCGAAUGCUGGAUAAGCCAUUAAACUUAGCAUUAUCUUCAUCAUGGGAAAACACUUAUUUUACUUUCGAUUUUUUUUUUCCAUAAAGGAAAACAUCACUUCCUGAAUUACUGACCCAAGCCAAACAGAAACAAUAACCCUCGAGAAAAUAGGUCAACAAUCUGUUGUGGGGAAACCACCUCCAUGUAACCCACUGGAUACAGUCCCCUUAAUGUUUUUGCUUCUAAAUUGUACCUUUUGCUUCUGAUUUCUUCUCCCCUGCUGUUUCCUGCCCAUCAGAGAGGCCUGAUACAAGCAAGUUUGUUUACAUCCCUGGGGAAUCUUUUACAUCAAACUUUUGGGAUCCAAAUCCAUCUCCUUUUAAAUUUCAAUCUCAGCACCUGCCAGUUAUGCAAAUGCCAAAAUGUGGGUCAUCAUAUAGUAUAUUUGAAACCUUUCUGAACAUGUACACCACCCAAUGCUAGAGGCUGACUUGGAAACCGGUGGGUGCAAUGCCCGAGGCUGUGGAACAAUCAGCCCAUCUCUUUGUGACCUGGAGCAGUCAGAGGGCCCUCAGUCACCCCGCCCCAUUCCUCACCAGAGAAAAGAAUCCAUUUCUAUGGAAGCUCUGACGUAACUUCAGUGUUUUCUACAAUACUCCUCCUGCCCCGCCCCAUUAAAACAGUUCUUUUGUUAAGAAAUAGCCUAAUGGUCCAACUUUGCUGUCUGUUCUUCCAAAUGUUUAUAAUACACAUUAUUUAUAAAUAUGUCUGUUUGGGAAGCUAAGAACAAGCUAGUUUUUACAACACAAAUGGAAAUAAAUGCAAUUAUUAUAAAAAUUCAA